CUCACUACCGAAACUCACCGAAGGAAACAGACGCCAGUGCUCCUCCCGGGGCUGCCACCACGGCUCCGGCAGGCGGGCCGGGGACCGGCCGAACCUGAGUUGACGGUGGAGGGGCUCGGGUUAGCUAGAUGGGCGGUUGGUUAGAUGCGUAAGCGGUAGUAUGCGAGCUCAGUUCGUUGUUGCUGGUUGGCUGUCUAGUCGGCCGAUCCGUCUGCUCACCCGGCCUGCCCUUUCCUGCCUUUCGUCUGCAGCGGCCGCCAGCUCCUGCUCGGUGUCCAAAACAAAAUGGCCGCCACGUCCAGUGCUUGUCUGACCGGCUAAAAUGGCGUCUACGCAAUUACGUCAGGCGUCAGAUCCGCGCACGACUAGAGGGCGGGAAAGAUUUGAGCUACGCCUGCGCAGAGUUGAGAAGCUGAUGUCUCCUCGACUUCCAACUGGAACCUUGAACCCCCACAUUUCUGGACCUUGAGCAUUCCUCAAGUAGGAAGAUGUAAUGCACCUUGACCUCUUUCUAAAUAAGACACUUCCCCAAAUAAGGGGAGUUGAGAGUGAACAGUCUUCACGUCUCCACCCACUUCCAGAUCCCAGAGGAGACAGACAUCGGAUGGCUGUUACCUCCUCCUAAAAUGUCUGCAUUUACCCAGAUAAUCUUCCAAUGGAAAUCCAUGGUUCAAGUGCCACCUCUUCAGGAAAGCCAUCUGACUUCAAUCAGGCAGCAGUGGAUGGUGCAGGGGAAAGAGGUGGGAAGGAGGUCCUGGGAGGGACACUGGAUGUCUUACCCCAAGCUGGGCCUUGCAGUACCUGUGGCUGGCUGUGCUGGUUGAGCCCGAAUCGACCACGGAAAUUUGACACCUCCGGGCUUGGAAGCAGCUCUCUCCUCCUUCCCCGCUGCUUAUAAACCUCAGCCCUGAGGCUCCAGCUCACUCUACCCCAUCUCCUUGCCGGGUGAGUCUCAUGGCUGACCCUGGAGGGAGGCUGGAGAUCAUUUUUUCUUCCUGGGCUCCCAGGUCCCUCCCCCAGAGCCAGCUCAGACAGGAAUUCAGGAAGGAGCUUUGGAUGAUCGAGCAACAGCGCGUGCAGGAGUGUGUGACGGGGUGGACAGAAAAGAGAAUGCCUCUUCCAGCCCCACCCGCCGCACCCCAGGGGGUUGUGAGUGCCUGUACUAAACCCGUCCUGGAGCAGGGAGUCAGAGACGCCCCGUUCCAGGACCCUUGUCACCGGGAGACAGGAGCGGGGAGGAUCUGUGGGGUCCUGGGUUCAGCACUCUGCCCUGCUGCCGCUGAGGAGAGGUAAGGGUGGAGCGGGGCAGAGAAAAUGGGUCUGUUCAGACGGAGCCAGCUCUGACCACAGGGGACAUUUGCCAGACCCUGUGCUUCUCUGCUGGGAGGAGCGGUUAGAGUGUGUGUGGGCGGAUGCGAGUGGCCGGAGACCAGGGCCCAACAUAAACAAGCUUUGGAGACAAACAACCUUAUGACCUGUCAGCCCUGACAAAGGUCAGCUAGCCCCUUGAGGACAUCAGCUUUGGCCUCAGGGUCCUAAUGGCAGCAGAACCACUGACAGAGCUAGAGGAGUCCAUUGAGACCGUGGUCACCACCUUCUUCACCUUUGCAAGGCAGGAGGGCCGGAAGGAUAGCCUCAGCGUCAACGAGUUCAAAGAGCUGGUUACCCAGCAGUUGCCCCAUCUGCUCAAGGAUGUGGGCUCUCUUGAUGAGAAGAUGAAGAGCUUGGAUGUGAAUCAGGACUCGGAGCUCAAGUUCAAUGAGUACUGGAGAUUGAUUGGGGAGCUGGCCAAGGAAAUCAGGAAGAAGAAAGACCUGAAGAUCAGGAAGAAGUAAAGCCGCCUGGCUGAGAUGGGGUGGGCAGGGCAGAGCUGAUCAGGGCCGAGCAGAACCGCACUCUUCCCAAAUAAAGCUUCCUCCUUGAAACACAAA